UGGAGAUGGGUCUCGGUAUGUUGCACAGGCUGGUCUUGAACUCCUGGCCUCAAGCUAUCCUCCUGCCUCCCUAAGUGUUGGGAUUACAGGCAUGAGUCACUGCACCCAGACUGCCUUCAAUCUUUUUGAGUAGGGAAGAUAUAUGAUACCUGCUUUAGAAAGAUAAUACAAAGUGGGGAGAGGAUGAAGUGUGUGAUGGCGGUCUGCAAGACUGCUACAGAGUUUACGGGCUAGGGCUAGGAGUUAGGUUGUGAGGCGGUUGCCUGAGGAUAGAGUGUGAUAGAGAUUUAAAAAAAAAAAUAACAGGAGGAAAAUAACAGACGAGGAGAUUUAGUUUGUCGAGUACCUGUUAUGUGCCAGAUACUGUGCUAAGAACCUAGGAUUGACAGAGAUGGAGACAGGGCUGUAAACAUGGCUGAGAAAGGGUACCUACUUUCCAGAAGUUUGCAGGUAAGAAGGGAAAUGAACAUGUAAGUAACUAAUAAAAUCCAGUAUGAGAUACACAGUAGUAGACAUAUAAACAAAUUAGAGAAGUAUGUUGGAGGAGGUAACCAACACUGUUGGAAGACAGGGUGGUGAUCAGGGAAGUCUAUCUAGGAAGCUUACAUAAAAUUACAGAAGAGGAAUACAGUUAAACAUAAGCUUCUCUGUCCUUCAGUUGCUCAGGUAUCCUUCACAAGAUAGGAUAUGAACAGAGAUGUUAAAGAUUAGUAGCUGUUUUAGAAGCUGACUAGUUACUUUUGUUGAGAAAUAUAGUGGAGAUGUAAAUCUUGGCUCUGCUACUUAACUGGUUCUGUGGUUUUGUAUUUUUUGACAGACUCUCUCAGUCUGUGAAAAGGAAAUAAUAGUGCCAACCUCAUAAGACUAAAUUACAUAACUCACUUAAAGCACUUAUUAGAGUACCUGGUGUGAAGCAAACUCAAGGUAGCUUGAUGCUGCUCUGAAAAAAGAUGCCUGGUGCACAGCAAACUCGUGUCUUCUUGCUGCUGCUGUUGCUGCUGGCUGCUGCCACUGCUGCUGCUGGAGGAAGCUCAGCAUAAAGUUUUGUGGGAGGAAUGUGUCUGGAGAUGAUCAUGAAGGGACUUCUAAUGCUAAUGGGUGUUACCUUUUAUCUUUCAGGUGCUAGUUUUAAGCAAGGGAAUUAUAUGGUUGGAUUUGCUUUUUAGGUGGGUUAUCUGAGGGUAAUAUGGAAAAUAGAUCUGAGACUGACUUCUAGAGAUCAGUUGGGUUAUUGUAAUAAUAAAUUGAGGGUUUAAUCUGUGUGGUGGGGUUGUAGAGGAAAGUAGACAGAUUUGUUAACUAAUUAGGACUUAAUUUUUUACAUGAAAUCUGUCUUUAUUUCCUUGAUUAGGAAGUAGGAGUAGUAAGCACGUAAAGGUAGUUGUUGAGAGAAUGUUAAGAAUGACUCCCUAGCUUUUGUCUUAGAAGAUUAAAUGGAUAGUGAUGUGACUAAAUACAUCAGAAAAUACCAGAAGAGGAUUUUUUUUUUUUUAAGAGAUAGGGCCUCACUUUGUUGCCCAGGCUGGAGUGCAGUUGUGUGAUCAUAGCUCACUGCAGCCUCAAAUUCCUGGGCUCAAGGGAUCCUCCUGCCUCAGCCUCCCAAAGUACUGGGAUUACAGUUGUGAGCCAUCACACCUGGCCAGGAAGUGGAUCUUUAAAGAAGAUGAUGAUGAGAACAGUGUUUGAGCUGCUAGGGGAAUCCCAGAAAAUUAAUAGCAAAGGCUUUGACUAAAAAUAAAUGGGAUUUAGGAGAGUAGGGCUGAAGGUAGAUUUUGGAGUGGUCAGAAGGUUAAGUUGUUAAAGCCAUGGGAAUUGAUAGGAUCACCCAAGUAUGUAAUGUAACAAAAACAAAGAGGGCCUAGGGUGGACACCUGAAACACCAUAUUUAAAGGACAUAUAGAAGGAGGGAAUUCGUCUGAGAUUCUUUUCAUGUACUUAUGAAUUUUUUAAAACAAUUUCUUCUUGUUACAUAAUCAUCUAAGAUUCUAUAAAAGAAUGGUCAGAGAAUUAGAAGGCAGAUCCUAGGUGUUUUCAGAAGCCAAGGAAGUCAGUUCAAAGGAGGACUGCUAAGUCUCCACUGGUUUGUCAUUUGGGGGGUUAAUUAGUCCUUGUGAUAGCAGUUUCCUUAAAAUUGGGGUGAUAGCAGGUGCAGUGUGUCAAAGAGAGGAAAGAUUUCUUGAAGUGGAAUUAUGGAUCACAAGAAGGGUUACAUGGGAAUUGGUCUUUCUGCUCAAGGUGUGAACAUGAAUAGACUACCAGGUUGGGAUAAGCAUUCAUAUGGUUACCAUGGGGAUGAUGGACAUUCGUUUUGUUCUUCUGGAACUGGACAACCUUAUGGACCAACUUUCACUACUGGUGAUGUCAUUGGCUGUUGUGUUAAUCUUAUCAACAAUACCUGCUUUUACACCAAGAAUGGACAUAGUUUAGGUAUUGCUUUCACUGACCUACCGCCAAAUUUGUAUCCUACUGUGGGGCUUCAAACACCAGGAGAAGUGGUCGAUGCCAAUUUUGGGCAACAUCCUUUCGUGUUUGAUAUAGAAGACUAUAUGCGGGAGUGGAGAACCAAAAUCCAGGCACAGAUAGAUCGAUUUCCUAUCGGAGAUCGAGAAGGAGAAUGGCAGACCAUGAUACAAAAAAUGGUUUCAUCUUAUUUAGUCCACCAUGGGUACUGUGCCACAGCAGAGGCCUUUGCCAGAUCUACAGACCAGACCGUUCUAGAAGAAUUAGCUUCCAUUAAGAAUAGACAAAGAAUUCAGAAAUUGGUAUUAGCAGGAAGAAUGGGAGAAGCCAUUGAAACAACACAACAGUUAUACCCAAGUUUACUUGAAAGAAAUCCUAAUCUCCUUUUCACAUUAAAAGUGCGUCAGUUUAUAGAAAUGGUGAAUGGUACAGAUAGUGAAGUACGAUGUUUGGGAGGCCGAAGUCCAAAGUCUCAAGACAGUUAUCCUGUUAGUCCUCGACCUUUUAGUAGUCCAAGUAUGAGCCCCAGCCAUGGAAUGAAUAUCCACAAUUUAGCAUCAGGCAAAGGAAGCACCGCACAUUUUUCAGGUUUUGAAAGUUGUAGUAAUGGUGUAAUAUCAAAUAAAGCACAUCAAUCAUAUUGCCAUAGUAAUAAACACCAGUCAUCCAACUUGAAUGUACCAGAACUAAACAGUAUAAAUAUGUCAAGAUCACAGCAAGUUAAUAACUUCACCAGUAAUGAUGUAGACAUGGAAACAGAUCACUACUCCAAUGGAGUUGGAGAAACUUCAUCCAAUGGUUUCCUAAAUGGUAGCUCUAAACAUGACCACGAAAUGGAAGAUUGUGACACCGAAAUGGAAGUUGAUUCAAGUCAGUUGAGACGCCAGUUGUGUGGAGGAAGUCAGGCCGCCAUAGAAAGAAUGAUCCACUUUGGACGAGAGCUGCAAGCAAUGAGUGAACAGCUAAGGAGAGACUGUGGCAAGAACACUGCAAACAAAAAAAUGUUGAAGGAUGCAUUCAGUCUACUAGCAUAUUCAGAUCCCUGGAACAGCCCAGUUGGAAAUCAGCUUGACCCGAUUCAGAGAGAACCUGUGUGCUCAGCUCUUAACAGUGCAAUAUUAGAAACCCACAAUCUGCCAAAGCAACCUCCACUUGCCCUAGCAAUGGGACAGGCCACACAAUGUCUAGGACUGAUGGCUCGAUCAGGAAUUGGAUCCUGCGCAUUUGCCACAGUGGAAGACUACCUACAUUAGCUAUGCAUUUCAAGAGCUCACACUUAUAUUGUGGCAUAUAGUCAACAUGGAAGUAGACCAGCUCUGCUGAUUUGAAAUUUAGAUUUUUUAAAUUAUGUACUGGGGACAGGUUUUUGUCGCUUUACAUUGCUUCCUAGUUUACAGCAUGAUGCAAAUGAUUUUCUAACUUAGUGUUAGGAGAAAUUAUUUUCCAUCUUUAACCUCUUAGUUGUCUAAGAGUUAAAUAUUACUGAAUUUCAGACGUUCAAAUUGAUCAUCACAAAUCCUUUAAAACAAUUACCUAAAAGAAACCAAAAAUCCUGCCUUCUUUGUGGGGGAGGGGGGAGAGAGGGGAAGGAAAUGGAACAAGUUGUGUUUGUGUUAGCAUGUGGGUGAUGUAAACUUCAAAUUGGGAGAUGUUCCGACCCCCACUCCCAUAUAAGCAUUCAAUCAGUGUAACUUGCAAAAUGCAUAAACAUCCGACAGUUUGAAUUUAUAGUGUUGAUGGAAGAAAUCAUUUUUAAUGUGUACUGUAAAACUUGAAAUACUCAGGAGCUGAGUGAAUAUGUUUGUUGCUACUUACAAUCCCGACCUGUUAGUCCCAGUAGUUUUGUUUUAACAUGGUCUUUUUCAACUUUGUUUCCUGUUUAACUACAGAUGACUUCUGUUGUAGACUCACAAGUUUAACUGUUGUAUUAUAACAGUAUUACAUGUCAACGGUGUGGUUAUGACCUUUAUUUAUAUAAAAACCAAAUAUUUAGUCAAUUUACCGUGUCUUAAUUUAAUCUUUGUACACCUUCCAUUUUUAAGUGCUUAAAUGAGUACUAUAUUGCAAUAAAAUGUAGUGAUAUAAUUAACCAGCCAUUAAAAAUUUACUUCUACAGA